GUAAACUGAACUGGGGCUGGGCAACAGGAAAAAAGAAGAAACCACAGAUUAGAGAAAUCUCGGCGGUCAGGAGGCCCGGGGUCUAAGAUGUAAAGAGGUAAACAGAUUUAGGGAUUGAUUGUCUGCUGGGGUGGGUUGAGAGGAGAAAAGGGAAGAAAAGUCGGGGGACUACGUCCUCAGACCUGACCUGAGUGGUGAGAGGUGGACCCAGGAGGAGUGGCAGGUGGUGGCGGGGUUUUGCAGAGCUCAGUUGGAGGCCCUCUCCGAGGCAGCUUGAUGGAACGUGGGAGAGCCGGGCUGGAGUCACAGUUUUUAUUUUGCUAGGGAGGUAGUCAGUGGCGCACAAAGGGUAACAAGCAGUGAUAGUGGGGAUGCUUUCCAUUUUAGGAAACUUUUCCUAAAAGGAAGUGGCAAUUUUAACUAAUCUCCCCUCCGCCGCUCCCAGCUGCCGCUCCAGAUGCUGCUGCUGCCGCCGCGGCCACCCCACCCUCGGUCCUCCUCUCCGGAGGCCAUGGACCCACCGCCCCCCAAGGCUCCCCCUUUCCCCAAGGCGGAAGGCCCCUCCUCCACUCCUUCCUCGGCGGCGGGGCCCCGACCCCCGCGGCUGGGCCGCCACCUCCUCAUCGACGCCAAUGGGGUCCCCUACACAUACACGGUGCAGCUGGAGGAGGAGCCCCGGGGCCCGCCCCAGCGCGAGGCGCCCCCAGGAGAGCCCGGCCCUCGCAAGGGCUACAGCUGCCCGGAGUGCGCCCGUGUCUUUGCCAGCCCUCUGCGGCUGCAGAGCCACCGCGUGUCGCACUCGGACCUCAAGCCCUUCACGUGCGGCGCCUGCGGCAAGGCCUUCAAGCGCUCCAGCCACCUGUCGCGGCAUCGCGCCACGCACCGCGCCCGCGCCGGGCCGCCGCACACCUGCCCGCUCUGCCCACGCCGCUUCCAGGACGCCGCGGAGCUGGCGCAGCACGUGCGCCUCCACUAAGCUCGAGACCCGGCCUGUGCUGCCCUGCCCGUCUCAGGGCCACCAAGUCUGACCCACACAGCGUCACUCACUCCCACACACACCCCCUGGCUCUGCUGAGGUUACUGCCUUACCCUGGGCCUCAGUUUCCCCACCUUCCAAAGGGAGGAGCAUCAUUCCUUCCUUACCCCCUUUCUAGCUGUGUGAUGUAGACCAAAGUCGUUGCCCCUCCCUGGGCCUGGGAACCAGUCGGAACUGGGUUCCAGUCCAGCUGUGCUGUGUGAGCCUGUGCAAGUGACAUGACCUCUCUAAACCUUGGUUUUCUGCUCUCUGGAGCGGUGAACCGGUGGUUGUCUGCGGGGAAGAGAUGAUAAAGAGCACGGGCACGGUCUGGUUCAUUUCUGUAUCUACCCCCCUUCCGCCCACGCCCCCGACCCUUUGCUCAAUAAACAUUCCGCACUCCA